ACUAGGGAGCGGCGAGCCGAGACGGCUACAUGGACGCCACUAUCGCCCCGCACCGUAUCCCCCCCGAGAUGCCCCAGUACGGGGAGGAGAACCACAUCUUCGAGUUGAUGCAGGUAUUAACCACCUGGGUGUCUGCCCUGCACCCACAGAACAUGCUGGAGCAACUCCUGAUCCACCAGCCCGAAGAUCCCAUCCCCUUCAUGAUCCAGCACUUGCAUAGAGACAACGACAAUGUGCCCAGGAUUGUAAUAUUAGGUCCACCCGCCUCAGGGAAAACAACAAUAGCAAUGUGGCUCUGCAAACAUCUGAACAGCAGUCUCCUCACCCUGGAGAACCUGAUCUUAAAUGAGUUUUCCUAUACGGCCACCGAAGCCAGAAGGCUUUAUCUGCAAAGGAAGACAGUUCCCAGCGCGCUGCUCGUCCAGCUGAUUCAGGAACGCCUGGCUGAAGAGGAUUGCAUCAAGCAGGGCUGGAUUCUGGAUGGCAUCCCUGAGACGCGUGAGCAGGCUCUGAGGAUCCAGACCCUGGGGAUCACACCCAGACACGUCAUUGUGCUGAGUGCUCCAGACACGGUCCUGAUCGAGAGAAACUUGGGGAAGAGAAUCGACCCUCAAACUGGAGAGAUUUAUCACACCACCUUUGACUGGCCACCCGAAUCUGAAAUCCAGAACCGUCUCAUGGUGCCAGAGGACAUCUCAGAGCUGGAGACGGCUCAGAAACUGCUGGAGUAUCAUAGGAACAUCGUCAGGGUCAUUCCCUCCUACCCCAAAAUCCUCAAAGUCAUCAGUGCUGACCAGCCAUGUGUGGACGUCUUCUACCAGGCUCUGACCUAUGUCCAAAGCAACCAUCGUACUAAUGCCCCGUUCACCCCGAGGGUGCUGCUGCUCGGGCCUGUGGGCAGUGGGAAAAGUCUGCAGGCCGCCCUCCUGGCCCAGAAAUACAGGCUUGUCAAUGUCUGCUGUGGGCAACUGCUGAAAGAGGCUGUGGCAGAUAGGACCACGUUUGGCGAGCUCAUCCAGCCCUUCUUUGAAAAGGAGAUGGCAGGUGCUGCCAACACCUCCUUCUUUCGAAUCAGCAGCAAAAUUAAUAACUGUACUGUUUUCCCAUCUUUCCACAUUUACUGGGCAAAGGACCCCAGGGCCCCAUCUUAGCGCAUCUUCAGUCCCUUGAUCCCAGGCUCUUGGUGAUGGCACUGUGGACAGAGGACUGGGGAGAUGCUUAUUCUGUGCCUGGACUUUGAAAUAUAUAGGUCUGACCCCCUAAACUCGUUCUGACUUGAGCUGCAGUGAACAGAACAAAUUUAUUCCCCAGGGCUCCGCACGUGGAGUUCUUUAUGCAGGCAACCUCCAUUAAAGUCACCAGGAGUUUGCUCUGCAUACGAUAAACAGGGUCGAGCUUAAAUCAUGCAGCCUUAGUUGCCAGGGAGCUCCUGUCACUUUUACACUAGUACAAAACAAGUAAAAACGAUUCUGGGCUUUUGGAAAAAUAAGUUCUCAGCUGUUUCUGUAUCAUUUAAAAUGAGAUGGUUGCUGCUGAUGGACUCCAUUGCCACCGUGUUCUACAGCAUGUGUACAGAUGUCCUCUUUCCUCUCUGAACUCAAGCAAAGGCGCUACUAGAUCUCAGUUCUUUGCUUAAAUCAGCGGUGGCUCACAGUGGCCACCACUGCCAAAUGAUGUCCUCAGCUCCUUCCCCAUAGCUCCAUUCCUACCGAAGUGUGUUUGAAAUUUCUGAAUUCUGGAGGCCCAGAGCUUCCUAAGGAAAUUGGCCAUAAUUCUGUCUUUGCCUCUUGGAAUGUCGCUUCCCGAUUUUCACUUAAUAUAAAAUGAGCCCUGCUCAUGGGCCUCACUCUGUUGUUCAAACUCACCCAACAUAAAGAAGUCUGAAGUCUGCACUGCUUUAUUUUUAGCCUUUCUCAUGAGAAUUUUAGCCAUAAAUUAGGGUCCAGGGACUGUUGAUGGUGGAUAUAACCUACUUCCAGGUUGCCGGGCCCAGUGAAUGGUACAACGCCGGCUCUUCAGCCAGAAGGCUUGGCUUCUGCCCUGGCCCAAGGAACUGUUCUCGUUCUCAUGAGUUGCUUGGACUUCCUCUGGAGGGUGGUUAUCCAGGGAGGAGAUGAAAAACAGCCAAAGGCAGAUCUUGUCCUUGCUGGUUUAUGUCUUUGCUCCAAGUGCAUGAGAUGCUCAUCUCAGCCUGUCCACAGCGCACUCGGAACAUGCUGGAACUGCAUGGUCAGGAGCCCGCCAGCCAUGCCAUGUCCCCAGCAGUGGGGCUUCUGAGCUAGACUGUAGCUUUUCACAUCUCCUGUCUCUGCAUACACUCUGCAACACCUGCCCAACUGGCUCGUCGGCCCAGUUACGGUGAGCUCCUAACUGGCAGCUGCCCCUGUGGCCCCGCCCCCCCCAGCAUCUCCCAACAGCUAAAGCAGUUCAGUUGUAGGAAGGCCCACAUUCCUUGGCACAUACCAGACAUAUUCCUUUCUUAUUGUCAGGAGGGAAGACAGCUAUUUAAUUGGUAAUGACUUUCCCCUAAAAGCGAAAGUCCUGGUAUGUAGAAAAGGUGAUGUGGAAGACAGAUCAUUAUCGAGUUGUUACCUGUGCCCCUCCCACACAUCCCUACAUUUCCUAAACAUUUCUGUCUGGGAAAGGUCCCUCAUGGCCUAAUAGAACCCGAGAAAAGGCGGGAGAUUUGAGAGAGUUUCAAGAAGCUAAUUUGCACCCUUUCUGGUAAUGAGACCUCACCCUAGCAAAUGCAGCCAUCGUAAUACAAACAAGCCAAACCAGCCCCCAAUUGGGAUGAUGAUGUGUUUUCAAGAGCCUUCCGUGAGUCCAGAUCCCAGGAGGUGUGGAUCAGAGCUCAGCCAAAGUGCUGCAUUUUUAAGGGGGAAUUAAUAUUCUCAUCACUAAAUGCACACUAAAGAUCGACCAUAGACCAGUUUUUCUCUUUUGUUAAAAACUUGCAAAGAGUUGCUGAGUUGAAAGACAAAGUAAAUCUCCCCAUCUGAGGAGGUAAGCGGAAUGCUAUUUCUUGUUUUUAGCAGAGCAGCCUCGGCCAGCUGCAAGCUGUCUUCCCGUGGAGGGGAGACCCUGAGGGACCCUCUGCCCGUUUCCAGCAAGCCUUUGCAUGCGGUGUGUUUGUACUCGCUGAAGACAGCGCAUGACUCUCUAAAUAAUUUACAAGUUGAUUAAUAGACUCACAGGGGUAUAAUUAGAAGAGGGAGAGACAGUGGGUACAGUAACCGGUACAGUGCUUGGGGGAACAGGAGCCUUUAUUUUUUUAAAGAAACUUUCUAGGGUGCUGGGCGUUUGAAGAUAAGUUGGGAAGAGCUCAGUGCCUCUUCUCUUUUGAAGUGGAAAUAGGACAGUUUGAAUCCGUCGAGUUUAAUUUUUCACAAGCUUUAGGGGCCCCGCAGUGCAACUCCCUUUUUAUUAUUGAAAAAACUCUACAUUUUUCUUUCAUUUUUCUACACACACACACACACACACACACACGCCAAGCAGUAAGUAAUAAACACAUUAAUUUACUCUUA